CCCGUCCCUGCGCCUCGUCCCCGCCGGGAGCCCGGGAGUUCGGGAGCCCCGGAGUGGCGCCCUCAGUGCGGCCUGUGCGGCCCGGGAGGGGCUGUUGCCCCGGGGCCCAGAGAGAGGCCGGAGGUGCGGGACUCGGACCACGGACCCGGUCGCCUCUUCCCGGCCAGCCGGGCGGUGCUGGACGCGUGACUCUAGGCGCGCACCUGUGAGGACGUGAGCUGUGGAUUGACAGCCGGACGCCAGCAGUGCCCACCUGGGGUCGCCCCCAACCUCCUCUCCCACACUUCGAGCCGGCGUUUGGGUGACCGUGAACCAGGAGAGACAGCUGUGGCGGGCCGGGAGCGGUGGCUUAUGCCUGUAAUCCCUGCACUCUGGGAGGCCUAGGAGGAAGGACAGCUUUGAGCCCAGGAGAUGGAGACCAGCCUGGGCAACAUAGCUAGACCCCUCUCUACAAAAAACAAAACAAAAAAAACACUUAGGUCGGCGUGGUGGCACGCGCCUGUAGUCCCAGCUACUCUGGAGGGUGAGGCGGGAGGGUCACUUGAUCCCGGGAGGUUCACUUGAGCCCCGGAGUUUGAAGCUACAGUGAGCUAUGAUUGAGCCAUUGCACUCCAGUCUGGGUGACAAAGCAAGACCCUGUCUUAAGAAAAAAAAAAAAAAAUCCCAAACAAAAAACUCCCACCUGUGUCAUCAGCUUUUUGUCAGAUGUCCCCAAAUUUACAAAAACUGCCCUUUUCCCUCUCCAUCUUCUGUCAGUUGGUUGCAUCAUUCACCAACUUGGGCACCCGACUGAUGGUCUUUGCGUCUUUUAAAUUUCAGUUGACAGUCAGCCUUUGUUUUUUUUGACCCAGUGCUUAGGAUGGUGGUUACGUGUUCAGCCCACUCUGUCACCUACCUUGUGACUUGGGCCAGUCAAUUAAUCUCUGUAAAAAGUCUGCUGCCUUGCUGUAAAGGGAACAAUAGAUCUUUCCAUUCAGCUGUUUUUGGAAAUGGGCUUAGCUUCACAGUGCAGUACUGCACAAAAUUUCAUGGACAUCGGUAGCAUUGUUCUCAUUAAUAUUUAAACGUGUUUUGCUUUUAAUCUGUUUCUUGUCCCUUUCCUCUGUUUUCUGGAAUAUUGCCUCACUUUUAGCACUAAAAUGACGUUUUCUGCAUAUGUCACACCGUAAAGCCCCUGUGGGGAAUUGAAUCUUAUCUCAGGUUUGAACAUUGCCUGGAGGCUGUGCUUAGAUAUGGGUUGAAAUUGUGCCACUAGCAAAUAAAAAAUACUCUUUCUUGUUAGUACCAUAUAUGUAUUAUGUCACACUGAAUAUGAAUGACUGUUUUCUCAGGUCCCCCAAGGUACUAGUUAUGCAAAUAACUAGUACCACCUCCACAUAACUGACACUACCCAGACAAAAGGGGAAGAAGUUCAUGCAUUACAUACAAUGUAUGGCUUAGAGCGUUGGGAAUUAACCUGAUUGAGAAAGAUAACUCAAUAAAAUGGCAAAAAAUUGAGGGGUGAGCUUUUUGUAGUAGUUUCCAAAUUGGAUCAAUUACAUUUAGGAUUUAAGUCAGAAUAGAAAUUUUGGACAUAUAAAAACAUGGAGAUGGGAAUGUCUGAUUUUCUUGGACAGUUUUACUUUUGAACAUUUUCAUGACUCCGCUGGCCUUCUGUUAACUACACUAACCAUAACUAGUGAUUUUCAGCCCUUGCCUACCUGUGCAGGCCGGAGUAGGAGUGGCCUGGUGCUUUCAUGGAUUCUGUAACUCUGCUCUGUCACUCUGCACAGUAAGCUUUGCCUACAGAUUUGGUUAGAUAUUGCUGCGUCAUUUCCUAGUUUUCCAGACUAGAUGGGAUGGCCAUGCUCUGCAUCCCUGUAGCCUUUAAAUCACAGUUCCUAUUCUAGUUCGUAUCUUUUUCUUAUUAGGAAAUGAGACUGUUUAGCAUAGCAGCUUGACCUGAAAUAGUAAAUUUAAUAGUUGUUGGGUUUAAGCUGUGAUGUUGAAGGUCUACAGGUGGAAAGCUUGACCAUUUAUUUGUGGUUGGCUACUGUUAUUUUGAGAUUUAAAAUAUGAUCAGGUUGAUGAUUUGGUGGAUAUCUCAGUCUGCUUGGGUCUACUUUUGAGGGAUACCUCAGUCUACUUGGGCUGAAAUAAGGACACACCUGAAUCUCAUGCCCAUAUGUUGAGAUGGAUCUCAUUCUGUCACCCAGGCUGGAGUGCAGUGGCGCGAUCUCCGCUCACUGCAAUCUCCACCUCCCAGGUUCAAGUGAUUCUCCUCCUUUGGCGUCCUGAGUAGCUGGGAUUACAGGCAUGAGCCACCACGCCUGGCUAAUUUUUGUAUUUUUAGUAGAGACAGGGUUUCACCAAAGUGUUGGCCAGGCUGGUCUCAAACUCCUGACCUCAGGUGAUCCGCCCACCUUGGCCUCCCAAAGUGCUGGGAUUACAGGUGUGAGCCACCAAGCCUGGCGUGUUCUCAUAUGUUAUACACUUAAAAUCAAAUGCAUGAAUACUGAAUAUGUGUGUUUAUAAUUGAAUGCCCUACAAUCAAUUGAUAAGUUUAACCAAAGACAGUUUAUACAAAUUGGCAGUAUCAAGCUUUUUGUCUGUUUAAUGUACACAUUCUAUGCUUGGAUAAAGUGGACAUACUUUUUUUUUGAGAUGGAGUUUUGCUCUUGUUGCCCAGGCUAGAGUGCAAUGGCACGAUCUCGGCUCCCCGCAACUUCUGCCUCCCGGGUUCAAAUGAUUCUCCUGCCUUAGCCUCCCGAGUAGCUGGGAUUACAGGCAUGCACCACCAUGCCCGGCUAAUUUUGUAUUUUUAGUAGAGACAGGGUUUCUUCAUGUUGGUCAGGCUGGUCUCCAAUUCCCAACCUUAGGUGCCUCAGCCUCCCAAAGUGCUGGGAUUACAGGCGUGAGCCACCGCGCCCGGCCUAAGUGGACAUACUUUUUAACCACUAUAUUGAUAAUUAUGUUUACUGAGGGAGGGGCAAAUUCUCCCCUAAAUUUUCAUUCAUUAUUUAGUUCAAUAGGUUUUUAUCAAGCAGAUUUGAACUGAUAUGCAGCACAGUGGAGCCUGCCUAGUUACCUUCGUUCUGGGUGAUGGUGAAAGCCUCCUGCAUACCCCGCUCAGAUUUCAUCUUUUUCUUCUCUGGCUAUAUCCUGUAUGUGAAAGCCUUUUCAAAUCAAUUUGCUGUUUUUCUUAGAGAGAUUUCAGGAAAGAAAACGAGAGAUAACUGGGUAUUUCUGAUUUGCUAACCAAUCUUGAUUCUAAUCUUCUUUUUGAAAAACUACAAUCACUCCUGACUGGAGUUUACAUUCCAUUAAAGUAUGUCUGAUUGCGUCUGCAUAUGGUAAAUGCCUUUCCCUGAAAUAGCUUUUCUCUCUGGAUUUAACUGCUGUGUGAGCAUCCAGAGACUUGCACACUUCCCAGAUCUCCGGGAGAGGAGCAGGGUUGAUUUCACUAUAAGGAAGGUGUAAAGAAAAACUGCCUGGUGCCCUGUGCUGUGAUGGCUGUAGGGAAUGAAGGAACAGCCCUUCAGGCUUCUUCCAUUGAAGACUUGAACAAGUGGGCCCUAUUUCUUGUGUCUCCUUUUAUACUUGAAGCAGAACACAUAGCAUUUGUGACGGAGAGCAUUUGGGUACAAAGUGAGAAUUUACAGAGAUCAUCCUCUUCAGAAACAAUUGUCAAGUGGUCAGACUGUUGUUUGCCAUUAGCUUGCAGACCUGGGGAUCCUUAUCGGCUAAUUGCUGAAGCAAGUGUGGACAACUUCAGCAAGCUGGGGGUGGCGUUCAUGGAAGAUAGACUCCACAUGGAUAAUGGACUGGUACCCCAAAAGAUUGUGUCGGUGCACUUGCAGGACUCCACUCUGAAGGAAGUUAAGGAUCAGGUCUCAAACAAGCAAGCCCAGAUCCUAGAGCCGAAGCCUGAACCUUCUCUUGAGAUUAAGCCUGAGCAGGACGGUAUGGAGCAUGUUGGCAGAGAUGACCCAAAGGCUCUUGGUGAAGAACCCAAACAAAGGAGAGGCAGUGCCUCUGGGAGUGAGCCUGCUGGGGACAGUGACAGGGGAGGGGGCCCCGUUGAGCAUUAUCACCUCCAUCUGUCUAGUUGCCACGAGUGUCUGGAACUUGAGAACAGCACCAUUGAGUCAGUCAAGUUUGCGUCUGCCGAGAACAUUCCAGACCUUCCCUACGAUUAUAGCAGCAGUUUGGAGAGUGUUGCUGAUGAGACCUCCCCCGAAAGAGAAGGGAGGAGAGUCAACCUCACGGGAAAGGCACCCAACAUCCUCCUCUAUGUGGGCUCCGACUCCCAGGAAGCCCUCGGCCGGUUCCACGAGGUCCGGUCUGUGCUGGCCGACUGUGUGGACAUUGACAGUUAUAUUCUCUACCACCUGCUGGAGGACAGUGCUCUCAGAGACCCGUGGACGGACAACUGUCUGCUGUUGGUCAUUGCUACCAGGGAGUCCAUUCCCGAAGACCUGUACCAGAAGUUCAUGGCCUAUCUUUCUCAGGGAGGGAAGGUGUUGGGCCUGUCUUCAUCCUUCACCUUUGGUGGCUUUCAGGUGACAAGCAAGGGUGCACUGCACAAGACAGUCCAGAACUUGGUUUUCUCCAAGGCUGACCAGAGCGAGGUGAAGCUCAGCGUCUUGAGCAGUGGCUGCAGGUACCAGGAAGGCCCCGUCCGGCUCAGCCCCGGCAGGCUCCAGGGCCACCUGGAGAAUGAGGACAAGGACAGGAUGAUUGUGCAUGUGCCUUUUGGAACUCGCGGGGGAGAAGCUGUUCUUUGCCAGGUGCACUUAGAACUACCUCCCAGCUCCAACAUAGUGCAAACUCCAGAAGAUUUUAACUUGCUCAAGUCAAGCAAUUUUAGAAGAUACGAAGUCCUUAGAGAGAUUCUGACAACCCUUGGCCUCAGCUGUGACAUGAAACAAGUUCCUGCCUUAACUCCUCUUUACUUGCUGUCAGCUGCGGAGGAAAUCAGGGAUCCUCUUAUGCAGUGGCUUGGGAAACAUGUGGACUCCGAGGGAGAAAUAAAAUCCGGCCAGCUCUCUCUUAGAUUUGUUUCAUCCUACGUGUCUGAAGUAGAAAUAACCCCAUCUUGUAUACCUGUGGUGACCAACAUGGAGGCCUUCUCAUCAGAACAUUUCAACUUAGAGAUCUAUCGCCAAAAUCUGCAGACCAAGCAGUUGGGGAAAGUAAUUUUGUUUGCCGAAGUGACCCCCACAACGAUGCGUCUCCUGGAUGGGCUGAUGUUUCAGACACCGCAGGAAAUGGGCUUAAUAGUGAUCGCGGCCCGGCAGACCGAGGGCAAAGGACGGGGAGGGAAUGUGUGGCUGAGCCCUGUGGGAUGUGCUCUUUCUACUCUGCUCAUCUCCAUUCCACUGAGAUCCCAGCUGGGACAGAGGAUCCCGUUUGUCCAGCAUCUGAUGUCCGUGGCUGUCGUGGAAGCAGUGAGGUCCAUUCCCGAGUAUCAGGAUAUCAACUUACGAGUGAAGUGGCCCAACGAUAUUUAUUACAGUGACCUCAUGAAGAUCGGCGGAGUUCUGGUUAACUCAACACUCAUGGGAGAAACAUUUUAUAUACUUAUUGGCUGUGGAUUUAAUGUGACUAACAGUAACCCUACCAUCUGCAUCAACGACCUCAUCACAGAAUACAAUAAACAACACAAGGCAGAACUGAAGCCCUUAAGAGCCGAUUAUCUCAUCGCCAGAGUCGUGACUGUGCUGGAGAAACUGAUCAAAGAGUUUCAGGACAAAGGGCCCAACAGCGUCCUUCCCCUUUAUUACCGAUACUGGGUCCACAGUGGUCAGCAAGUCCAUCUGGGCAGCGCAGAGGGACCAAAGGUGUCCAUCGUUGGCCUGGACGAUUCUGGCUUCCUCCAGGUUCACCAGGAGGGCGGCGAGGUUGUGACUGUGCACCCGGACGGCAACUCCUUCGACAUGCUGAGAAACCUCAUCCUCCCCAAACGGCGGUAAUGCCGGGCGUCCCCGAGACGCGGCUGCCUGUCCGUGCCCAUGCAUCUGGAAAUCUAAUUUAGAGUUGUAGGUGAAUUUUCUUUUCCUCCAAUUCAUUUGUUAAGUCUUUGUUCUUUUUCUGUGUUUCUGUUUGUUUUUAGGUUUGUUUUGUUGUCGUUUUCUUUGGUGUUUGAAGAGGCUCUGGGAUAGAUGGUUAAGAAGUAGAAAAUUUAGUUUAGGGAAAGCCCUCCCACAGGUGGGAAAUUGCUCUCCCCUCUGUGGCUUGGACUUACGUUUAUUGUCAAGGGGAGUUUUUACAUGGAAAUGACAAUGGGAAAAUUCAGAUAUUUUCUUAGUAGUGCAGACCUUUACCCCUAGUCUAUGAAAAAACAAACCAAAAUAUGCUCUUGCGCCCAGGCCAGUGGUGAGUUAGAGGUAUGCUAUCACUGUUUGUAAGCAUCUGGGGAGGUACUGAACUGUAAGAACAUGCUUGGACACUUAGUCAUUGUUCUGUGUUUUUAUUAAUGAAGAAAAGGGAAGACAGACUUCCAAGAGUUACUGUCCACCCGGUGGUGUGGCCCCAUAGCGAAGUCUAAAUGCCUGUAGAGAUAGAGCUAGCUGGUGUGGUUGCAGUGACCUUGUAGAGGAAAUCAGUUCAUUACUUUGACAUCAUUCAGUGAGCUCUCCUUUCCUAAGGAAGUUUAAAUGUCCUUAGUUAGGGACUGACUUUCUUAAGUAAGUUUAAAUUUACUACAUAUUGUGAAGAGACAGGAUCAAGUUCAGAAUCCUUAAAUGUCUGAUUAGGCAUCACUUGGAUGAGGAGGUGGGCGAUUUGGCUCUGACAGCUGGAGAUGAAGGCACACUCAUACCACAUACAAGGGAGGAUUUGGAGCUUUUAAGCCAGUUUCAGAUUUACUCUGAAAUGUGGAGCAUUCCUGCAAGACUGUGCAGCUCACGGAAUAUAGAAGACAUGGCAUUUUACUCAGAAGUCAUAAGUUUUUGCCCCCCUCAUUUACCUCGUAUUACCAAGAAAGAAAAUGUUAUCGAUACUAAACACCAUCAGUUCAGAGGGAGGAUGUGUGUGUGUGCCCGCAUAUGUGUGUGCGUGCGUGUGUGCGCACAUAGCUUUAAAAGAAGACAUUCAAAAUUUGAUGUGCUACAAGCCUCAUGAAAGAACAAAAGAAAUGAAGCCUUUUGAUAUGCAUUCGCUAUUCCCAGAUGUACGCCAUGCCUUUUCCAUGUCCCUCCUAUCUCUGUUGAACUUAUGAAUCAUACUCAUUACUUUUCAGCUUUUUAAAAGGCCAAUUUUUGUCCAGUUUUCUCUCUUCCAGUCCCAGCUGAAAUUAGUGGAAAGAAAGUUUGAUGGAGCUUUCAGCUUUGAACAAAAUCCCUUCAUUGUAAACUAGCACCAUCUUUAUCCAGGUCUUACCCAGUCAGGCUAAUUCCAGAAACUUGUGGUUUUUAGUAUAGUCUGUCUACCUUUAGCCAGGCACAGGACAGCCCUAUGAAAAAAUACCCAAUAUAUAUUUUUUGGAAAUGAAACAUUAAAAGAACUUAAAAAGUAAUUUUUGGAAAUGAGGCUUCAAUUAGAAUUAUUUUUCUCAAAAAACAAACAAACAAAAAACACAAAAAAAACCACUCUUCUCCAAAUGCCCAAGCCUUCUUUCAAAAUUAGUUAGAAACUUAAGUAAAAUACAAGUCCACACCAUCCCCAAAUUACAAAAUGGACUUACCCUUGAGAGGGCAUCUGCAGAAUAUCAUCAGGGACAAAGAUCUCGAGGCUAACGAUGUAGGUUUCAUUUCUCAGACUUUGUAAUAUAAGGCAAGCCCUCUCUCAGAGCUGCCAUCAUCACUUUUUGAAUUUCUUUGGGGGUUAUUUAAUGAAAAACAUGCUAUGUUUUGUUUUAAGCUGAAGUCCUAUUCUGGACACUCUGCUUUGGGAAAAAAUGUUAUCAUUUAAUUUCCUUUCUGCAAAUUAAAACUAAUGAAGUGUGGCCUUGUCAAAGGCUAUGGAGAUGUUCCGGGCAUACUGCUGUGCUCUGUGCUUUCCAGCAGGCGCUCCUCCCUCACGCAGGAGACUCAGUUGUCCUGAGAGAGAUGAAGCAGCCUUGAAGCAGAUGCUGCGUUUUCCAUAAACCUGAUUUUGCCUCACAUGAACCAAAGACUCUCAAAACUCCGCUUCUAUAGAAUUAGCUGAAUAAAGGCAUUUUACUGAUAGCUGUUCGUGUUAGCGAAACCUGUCUACCUGCUAUAGCACACUCUCCGAUUUGGGCCAUUUAUGCACCCCGCAACCUGGGAUCUCAAGGAGCUUUAAAGUCUUAAUGGGAACUUGGCAUUUUCCUGAUGAUCUUUAAAAUGUGGUCACUAAACUCAGGAUUGGCGUGUGCUUUUAGAACACUGGAGUAGCCCUUGUUUUAGAGGCUGUGCAUUGAGUAUCGACCGUAUUUUGUAAAAGGCAAGAUAUCCUCCCUUCCAGGCUGGUAACGGGUUUCAAGGGGACUCUUGAGGAAGUGCCCCCUAAAAUAGAACACAGCAAUAACUGGGCUUCCUGUCCCCACCCCCACCCCAGCAGUGCUCUCUGGCACUGGGAACUCUGCUAGGGAGUGGUGGAAGUAGGAAGGAUUUGUGUGCAAAGGAAAAUCGUGGUUGAGUUUCACUGCAGCAGGCUGACGUUGCCUGAUGUGAGAGCAAGUGGCCGACUGGGGUGCGGGUGCACAGGUCGGGGGAGCACAGGCCACAGAGCGCAGCCUCUGGGGGUCCCCCAAGGCACAGCAUAUACAGCAUGGUCGCCCCUUGCCCUGGAGUCUGGGAACAAAGAGAGGAGCCAGCCUCCCCGCACUGCUUCAGAUGGAAAAGGGAGGCAGGGUGGGCUUCCGUUCUCCAGAUCUGUUUGCUCUUAACAGGCAGAACAUGGGAGAAUCCUUAUUCCUGGUUAAUCACUAUGCAUAUUUGAAAUAAAAGAAAGCGUAAGCCUCUGCAAUUUUAACUUCUCAAAGGAUGUCUCUGAAAAGAAUCACUUUAAACCAAUGCCUAUAAAAAGCAAGUCUACCAAAAUAAACUAAGACUUUCUAUGUGGUUUGGGCUCCCUCUUAUUUUUACAAGUUUCAUUUUUAAAAGUAGGCAACUACUUUGGGUUACAGUAUUUUUAUUCAUAUUUAAACAUUUUUACAAAAUAAAUAAAGUGUUUUACAUAGUAAGGAAUAUGUACGUAUUUCCAAGUAUUAAGAAGCCAAGUGUUUUUUUUUUUGACGUAUUAUUGACAAAUGUAUUCAGCGCCAUACACAAGAGAAAUAUUAUUACUCCAAAGAACGAAAGUUAACAAAACUCCAAAGCAAAAACCCUUUUAAUGGAGGUGAGAAAUAAAUUUAAUGUAACAACAGCUAGAUUGUUUUUAGGAUUUUUCUUUUCUUUUGUGGAAACUUCUUGACUUGACUUUUCAUCUGAACAGUUUUUCCCCCCAAGAUUUUAAUCUUAUAUGUCAUACUUAAGUUUAGGAACAGCUUGAAUAAUUAGCAUUCUAGAUAACACAAGGGCCAUGAUUCACUAAAAUUCCAAGCUACUGUAAUUUUAUGGCAUUUAUUUGCAAAUGUUCUUUGUAUCUCAUUUUAUCUGUAGCAGUCCCCACUAGUCUACCUUAACCAUCUUAUAGCUCUGGUAAAUUAAAACUUACGUAGACUUUAUACAAGAUCCAUUGGCCGUAUUAAACCUCCCCCACUCUUAGGGCUUAGGGCGGAAGGGACGAAGGCAGGGCUGAUAGGACUUUUAAAAGGAUAAAAGGAGUGGGGGCAAGGGAGGCGGAAAAUACAGGCUCUUGCAGAUACCCUCCGCGCUGCCCUCCACACCCAGCCCACUGCUCUACAAAGGUAUGAAUGGAAUGGCUUUUCUAGAAAAGGGCUUCCAAGAACAUAAAGGAAUUCCUUUCCCUGGGAGGCCCCGUGGAGGGCUGAGCCAGCCUUGAAUUGGGCUUAUUUCUCAAAUCCAUUUGAUCUGGCAUUUUUGUCAACAUGGUACAUGUUAGGGCCUACGAUGAUUUUUUUUUCUUUUUUGUAAAAGAGAGGCAUAUGUAUUAAAAUGCUUCCUCUUCCCCUGCCGGAGCCUCACAGAAGUCAAGAAACGCUAUCCCCAGCUUAAAUGUGCAGACUCUUCAAGAUGGAGGUCACAAUAUUAGGUUGCCACAGUAACAGCUCUGCUGACUUCACACUCAGCCCUGGCCGUCCUGAAGCCAGCUCGUGUAAGAAUCUUCCUUCAUGUUCUAGGUUAUGAAAACGAAGUUUGUUUAGACAAGGACGUUUUCACUAGUACACAUUUUCAAGUACAUACACACUCUGUUACGCCUGUCCACGUUGUCACUUGUAAAUCUAUGAUAGGGUCUUUUUUCUCAACAGUAACCUUUGUUAUUGAACUGCUCCGAUAGCCUUGAUUUAUUUUUACUAAAUACAGCCCCAAAAGUUAAUAACAAGGUAGACACAAAAGCAUUUUGCAGUACUUUAUUGAAAAAUGUCGGUGGUAUCUCCUAGUAAUCAAACCUACACCUUUCAAGAAUCACGGUUUAAUUACAAGACUCAUGAACAUAAAAAAAUAAUACCCUCGGCUUAUUUCCUGUGCACACACUCACAAGGAGCUGUGAAUGAGGUAUAGCUGAGUGCGUGGAGAGGCGGGCACAUCCCUUCCUACCAUCCAGCCCCUUCGCUGCAUGACCCACGGUCCUAAAUUUGCAAAUUGUGACUCUUACCAUGAGGCCCACUGACAGACACCCUGUAGGGAUUGUGUCAGGUCCUCACUAAGUGACACAGGGUUGGCAAAAAAAAAAAAAAAAAAGUCAGUUCACAUUUUGAGAGCAGUUGGUGUAGGUGCACUUGAUUUUAGAACGAUGAGUUUAAAACAUUUGUGAAAACCUCUUUCCAUUCAGAAAGGUGGAAAAAGUUUCCUAAAAUAAACCAUUUUGAUAAAGCAGCAAAAUGCUGCAGUGUUGAUAGUGUGAAGAAAAUUGAAGGACGGCGGUUCAAUGCAUUGUGCAGUUCAGAGCCAUGACAGGAUUUUUCCAUGUUGAGAUCUUUAAGCAAAACCCAUAAAAAGUAAAAAUUAAUGGAAGCUCAUUUUUUAAACACUGCUGGUGCUUUAUGAAAGGAUUUCUGUUUACCUGUUGCACACGUAACAUGUUCUUACGAAGUUUUCUCGCUGUGUAGAAAAUGCUUAAAAUGUCUACAUCAUUUUCAUUACACCCCCUUAAGCAUGUUUUUCCUUCACAAGGUGCAGUCCAUUGACAGUGUUCCGUAUUGCACGUGCAAUUUAACUUUAUUAGCACUAUUUGUAGCAAACACGAGCCUAGUGAAUUACAGAUCUGUGUGGGCCAGAGGGAUUUUGCCACGUAAUAAUGAAGCUUGACAGGGUCAUUCUCAUAAACUGUCUGGCUACAUAUAUAUUUUUGCAUUUAAUGCCUAUUCAAUAUAUUCUGAAGGUGCUACUCUUGGUGUUAUCAAGAGUUCAUAGGGGUUAGGGGGAAGUAAGAGCUUGUUAAUGUAUUUGGGAAGCACACCUAUGUUCACAGACACAAAAUGGAAUUGCAUGGUCACCCCCUUAGUCUUGGUUUGUUGGCUUUUUGUAUUGAAGAAAGGGUUAAAUAAAAACAAAAAUAAUGAGAC